CUAGUCCUCUCCUACUGAUCUCCAUCGGUUAGCGCCUUGCCAUGAUUAAUCCAGAGCUGCGGGAUGGCAGAGCUGAUGGCUUCAUACAUCGGAUAGUUCCCAAGUUGAUACAAAACUGGAAGAUUGGCCUUAUGUGCUUCCUGAGUAUUAUUAUUACUACAGUUUGCAUUAUUAUGAUAGCCACAUGGUCCAAGCAUGCUAAACCUGUGGCAUGUUCAGGGGACUGGCUUGGAGUGAGAGAUAAGUGUUUCUAUUUUUCUGAUGAUACCAGAAAUUGGACAGCCAGUAAAAUAUUUUGUAGUUUGCAGAAAGCAGAACUUGCUCAGAUUGAUACACAAGAAGACAUGGAAUUUUUGAAGAGGUACGCAGGAACUGAUAUGCACUGGAUUGGACUAAGCAGGAAACAAGGAGAUUCUUGGAAAUGGACAAAUGGCACCACAUUCAAUGGUUGAUAUUUCUGCUGUUCAAGCAAAUAUGGAAAGACUUCUACUUAAUUGAAAAUCGUCAAAAUACAUUUCUGCAAUUUUAUGAGAAAAUAUCAAUCAAGGGUAUAUGGAUCUGUAGUUAACAAGUGCUCUUUCCAUACAUGCCAGGGAGGGAGACUUUAAACUUCUUGCCAAAUAAGAUUUAUAAAAAACUGAACAAUAGACCAAAAAUUAAUAUUUUCAUGUAAGCCAUGAUUUACAUACUAUAUCAAGCCAGGUGAACAGAGAGCUGAGUACAUGAAGUGCAGUAUGCUGGCCUAUCCUAGCACUGCUUGGCUAGAUGCCAUUGGCUUACACAGGGCUAUAUGAAGAAAUUGUCUUACAAAAUCUGCUGGUGCUACUAUUGCAAGAACACUAAUUGUAUUAUUUUAUGUGCUUCAUGAGAACUCAGGAAAAUAUUUUUUCUGAUUUAGGAUCAAGAUUAAUUAUAUCAAUCUUAAGGAAUAGGUGUAACUUUAUCUUAUACACAAUGUGAACUGAACAACUGGUAAGAAUUCCCUUAGGUCAGUAAUAACAAGGAAGCUUGGAAGCAAAUGUAUAGCAAGCACAAACAUGCCUACAGUAAUUUUUCUGGCCCAAUUUAUUUUCCCAGCCCUAUCCUUCCUUCAUUCAUAAUUUAAAUGGAUAUUAUCUUAUAUUUUAUGUAUCAAUACUCAGAUUUUAAGUCUCUGUACACAUUUGUAUAUUAAAAAGUAGUUUAUAGAUUAAAAAAUAGUAAAUUUAGUUUAACAUCCACAUAAAAGCAUCAUCAGGUAGAUUUUUCUUAUUAUAUAUCAAAGUAUUGAGAUUUAAGAAGGCUAAAAGCUUCUGCCCAGAGCCAUACAUUUAGUCUGUGGGCUUUAGGGUCUGAAUAAUUUUUUUUGUUUUUUUAUAUAUGGAGUCUUGCUCUGUCACUCAGGCUGGAGUGCAGUGGCAUGAUCUCAGCUGACUGCAACCUCCGUCUCCCGGGUUCAAGCGAUUCUCCUGCCUCAGCCUCCCAAGUAGUUGGGAUUACAGGCACACGCCACCAUACCCAGCUAAUUUUUUUUGUAUUUUUAGUAGAGACGGGGUUUCACCAUGUUGGCCAGGCUGGUCUCGAAUUCCUGACCUCAGGUGACCCGCCCACCUCUGCAUCCCAAAGUGCUGGGAUUACAGGCAUGAGCCACCGUGCCUGGUCUGCCUCAGUCAAUUUAACACCAAUGGUACUAGUUUUUGCUGCAUGGAAGUAAGUUACUAUUGAAAAAGUAAACAUUUGUUUCAUGAUAUUGAAACACAAAAAAGAUCUGAGUCUUCAGAUAAUAACAAAAGUGUCAUUUUGUGGGGGCAGGGGGUGCAGGGGAAGUUUGCAUUUGCUAGAUAUAAAAUGAGAUUGUACACGAGAAUGUUCAAUACAUAUGGCAGAACUGCCACUGCGACUGGUAAUUCUGAAUUUCUGGCCUAUGUCAUCUUAACUUAGGUCUUGGCUAUUUCAACAAGAUUGUUUUCAAAAUUCCUGAAAAAGCAAACAAAGCCAACCACAGAGCAGCCCUAAGGAGCAAAGAUUAAUGUUUUUUUGUUUUUUUUUCUCUCUUCUCGCAUUCCCAGUAGAUUGUUCUACCAAUCCUAUAGGGCUUUUACGAAGAUUAAAAAUAUUAUAUAUGUAUAAGCAUAAAUAUAUAUAUAAGCAUAUAUAUACGCUUUAAGUUUAUAUAAACUUUAAGUUUUGUAGGAGGAAGUUUCUGUAAAAACACAAUUUUUCAGCCUUUUCUUCGAAAGUGAUGUUCUUAUGCUACAACACACAGGAUUACACAUCGUCAUAUUCGCAUUUCUCUUACCUCAUGGCUCUGAAAAUGCAGACUUUUUAUUGUUGAUGCUUUCAUGAAUCUAAAUAAUCUAACAGACAAUUUAUGACCAUUUUUAUAUUCCUUAUUAUGAUCAAUGUUAAGAUGUUAAAAAUAUUCUAAGAUAAUUCUCUUCCUAGAAGAAUAAUGAAAUUUUAAAUGCGGUGAUGGGGAGCAGUAUUCCUACCUUUAGAUUUCUGCUUCGAUUUACAACGAUUCUUGAAACUCAGCGUCAUAUACCCAUCUUCAUUCUCCAUCUCUUCAAAUGUCUAAUGUCUUAUUAUCCAGAAAAUAGUACAAAGAAAAUGGAAACUAAUCUCAACCUUGGAUAUGUCUCUUUGGCACAAGGUACUAAAAGAAAACUAAAAGGAAGGCCAAAAAUAGUCAAAAUUUACUCAGACACAGAUGUCUAAAACCACACAGGAUGUGUUGGUAAAUGAAAAUGGAUAUAAGCUUGUUAAUAUCUGGCUACAAUUCUGUGAAUUUCAAGGUAAAGGUAGCUAGUGUGUUCCACUGUUUUCAACAAAUGGACUUGUGUGUUCCUGCCACUUGUGUGCGGUGUAUUAGAAACAUAAUUCCUUCCUUCAUGUCUUUUAUAAUAAAGUAAGAGAAAAAAUAAAAUAAAACAAAUAAUCUCUAAACAAACAGAACAAAUGUCUAGGUAAAUAAAAAUUCAAAUUAAAAAAGUUAAAAUAGCAAUUUUGUUAUUUGGGACAUAUUUGACUAGUAGAGUCCAAAUAACGAUGGUUAGAUGGGACAAAAAUAGGAAAAUAAAAGAUCAGCAAGUCUCAAGUUAGUGAAAAUCGGAAUCACUUGCAAAGAAUUUAACUUUUUAAACUUUUUUGUUUGUUUGUUUGUUUUUCAGAAAACGCCAGGCAGAUUUUCCUUCAGUAGGUGUGGCAGUUUAUUUUGUGUCAACUUGGCUGAGUCACAGAGAGUCCAGAUAGUUGAUCAGACAUCAUUCUGCUUAUUUCUGUGAGGGUGUUUUUGGAUGGGAUUCAUAUUUAAAUAGGUGACCUUUGAGUAAGGCAGAUUUGCCUCCUCUGUAAUGUGACUGGGCCUUAUUGAGUCAGUUGGAGCCUUGAAUAGAACAAAAAGACUUGUCUUCCCUGAGUGAGAGAGAAUUCUCCAGCAAUGGCCUUCAGACUAUCUGCAGCAUUAGCUCCUCCUGAUUCUACAGACGGUGGACUUUGCAUUUGAAUUGAGCCUUCCUAGGUACCCAGUCUGUCCAUGCUCAUUUGCAGAAUUUUGACUUACCAGCCUCCAUAAUCACAUUCCUUAUUUUAUAUAUAUUUCACUUAACACGCACACACACACACACACACACACACAUGCUAAUGGUUCUGUUUCUGCUACGUGGCCACUCAAUAUCAAUCCAUUGAUUUAACACCGAGUGUCUGGGGAAGGUGGCUGACUGUUUCCCACAGCACAUGUUGUGUUCACCUGAUUAUUGAGUCUCCUCCUCAACACUGGAUGUCACUUGUGAGUAUUUACAUGGGAAUGAAUAUUUACACACGCCGCGUCCAUUCUGCAUGAUCUCUAUAUGUACCUCUUAGCUUCUCAUUCAUUUUUCUAUUUUGUUCUUUUUGAGUUUCCGACAAGUCAUCUCACCUAUUAGUUUCUGAUAAGAUGAUUUAGAUGUAUUUCUCUGAGUGCUUAUCCUUCCUGUUAGGUUCACAACCAGACAUAUUGUCCAAACUUCUGUUCAGUGGGAAGACUUACCUUCACUUCUGUCUUUCACAGUCUUCUCCUGAAUGGGACUGUAGUGUGGCAUCUAUUCCAGCUGCCGUAUUUUACAUAACCACUGAUAAACUUAUUUUUUUCAACUACUUCAGUGUAAGAUCGUACAGAACCCUCUUUUCCAUCCCCAACCCGGGUCAUAGGUAUGGUUGAGGUGGAGAUAGCAAAGGAAUGCGAACAUGUGCCAUCGGAGUCUGAGCCAUCUGCUCAUGCAGUUUACUGUGCUUCUUUGGAACUGUUCAGGCCUUGCCUCCAAAAUGGCACAAUUAUGUUUGUGAUAAAAUGCUUCUGUGCACUUCUAAACAUAGGGUUCAUUGGGUCAAAGUGGUCAAGUUGGAUCAAGUUAAUGGUGGUGAACAUAUGUCUUAUAAAAAUAUGUAGUAGGUUUACUGCCUACUUUUCACCAGGAACAGUUGGCAUGAUAGCAUCAAUGUAAUGAAUCUAUUGUGUGCAACCAGUUCUGAGGUAUAACAUAUUGGGAGCUAUAUCAAGAUGAUUUAGUUCCCUCUGGGCCAUCUUAUAACAGAGAUCAGGAGAGCUGACAUACACCUGGGCAAGGCAGCAAAGAAAUACUUGUUAUUUCUGUUUGUAAAUACAAGCCGGAAACCAUCACAGGUUCUCAGCUUUUUCCCAGUGUAUAGUCAUUCAAGAAAAUGACUGAAGUUUCCUCCGGUUUAGGUGUUGGGGAAUAAAUAUCAUAAUUACACCUGUGGCCAUGUUACAAUGUCCUUCACCAAGAGACCAAACCUACCUCCUCCCCAGUUGAGUGGUUCCUGGUCUGCGAAGAGCUUUGCCUACUAACUAUAUGGAAGUCUGGGGAUUGGGUAAGACACAAUGAAUCUCCUCUCUGAAAAUACGGGCUAAGUUUCUGGGCAACAUACAUGUAAUUUUCCUUAGCAUAUCAAGCAGCUCCUUAGUGAAAUAUCCUUUUUUGUUUGUUUUUCUUUUCUUUUCUUUUUUUUUCAUUUCCCAAAACUUAAAAUCAGCUAAUCAUUGUCACAGAUUUCUGUGGAUGAAAACUCUGAUUACUAAUCAUUCCCUCUGGCUUAUUGUGGCAACUGCAACCCCUUGACCUCUAGAAUCAAAUUAUUGCCGUUGAUAUCAGAAAGCCUGAUUCCGCUGUAGCAUCUCCCAAUACAUCUAUAGUCAACAGUGAACAGUUGCCACAGCAGGUCGUCACCAGGUUCCCUCACAAAAGCAUUCUCCAUCCCCCCAUCCUCCUAAAAAAUCGGUUCACAAAACUGACCUUGAAGAGAGGAAAUCAAAGCCUGGAGGAGGCUGUAGAAAGGAGAGAGAAGGUGGUCAAUGACUGCCUAGCCUCCUCACUGUAUAAAAGGUAGCAACUUUAAAACUGUUCCCCCACCCUCCAUCCUGGGCGCCAGACCCCUCAGUUCUACCCAAGGGCCAUCAAGUACCUUCAGAAACUUCUCUUCCCUUUACCUUCUAUGCCUGGGCCAAUUCUCUCAGUAUGGGUCUAACAGAUUUGGUGGGAUUGAAUGCUGAAAUAUUUUAGAGUAUCAAAACUUGAAGAUGUCUAAAAUUUGUAUCUUAAUGUUUUUCCCAAACUAUAGAUUUAUUCAGUGUUCUCUAUAUAGUUAGUAAUUAAGUUCUGUCAGUUUAACCCCCUGCGUAUUUCCCUAGUAAAUUCAUUACUUCCCAUUUUAAAAGCCAUCAUCUUGGCUCAAACUCCGUGUGGGCUGACAUUAUUCCUUCAUGGCAUUUAGUCUCCUUUUGCCCUCUCCCCUUGGCCCAUAUAAAACAAAAGAGUAUCUUUAAGGGUUGAGAUACUCAAUAAAUCUGAUGCCCCACAAAUCCAAAAUAGACAUAGAAAAUGUGCAUCUUUUACAAAAUUCAUAUCCUCAUGUAUGAAUUAGUUAAUAAAAGGAAGUCUCCAUUCUCUCCAGAAACGUUACAACUUCUACGCUUCUGAAAUUUAGAAUUUCCCACACCCAUACCAGAUUAUCAUUUUAAUCUUAAAUGGGCAUUUUUUUUUUCAGACAGGGUCUUGUUCUGUUACCCAGGCUGGAUGUAGAGGUGUCAUCAUAACUCACUGUACCCUCAAACUCCUGAGCUCAAGUGAUUAUAGACACAUUUUUAAUCUGAUAGGCUGCUGCAUUGUUUCACUUUAGAUUUCUUGGAUUUUCAUUGUGUUUAGACAACUUUGGAUACACUGACUGUAUAUGCAUUGUUAUGGGUUAACUAUUUGUGCCUUGUUCAUUUUCUGUUACUAAUGUAUUUAUGACUAUUCCUCUGUAUAUAUUCAUUCGUAUAUUGAUUCAUUCAAUAAGACUUUUUGAAUAUAUGUUAUGCUACAGCCACAGUUCUAACCACUGAGAAUACAUCAACAAGUAAAACAGAUAAACCCCUCUGA